AACUGCUAUAGCAGAGAUGCGUGCAAAGUGCUCUGGGAGGAGCCACAUCUCCACAUGAGGCAGUUGAACGACGUUUCAGCUGAGUCUUGACAUGUGAGUUCAUCCAGGAAACGAAUAGCAGAAGAGCAUUUGACCAAGAAAAUAGUACCUACGAAGCUUGAAGGAUGGCUGGAGCUUAGGGUUUGUGAGACAGAACAUCAGGAAGUGAGCCCAGAAAGGUAAAUUGGCACCAGGUUAGGGAAGGUCAUAUUUGCCAAGGUAGAAAGUUUGCAUUCCAUAAGUGGAAGGCGACAAAAAGCAGGUUUGUAUUUUAGGAAAAUGAUUCUGGCAGCCUAGGUGGAUGUUGUAAGGUAAGAGCAUAGUAUUAUGCAAAAUAAACUACCGUGUUGUUGUCGGUUUUUUUUUUUAUCAUGGCCUUUCAUGAUGUCUAUUUCUUUUUCUCUAUUCCCAAUGUUCCUUUCUUCUGGUGAUGAUAUGCUAUAGAAAUUGUCACGGGUGAUUAGCAACUAUCUGGGGCUGGUGGCAUGGGGGUAAGAAGAAUUUAUCAAGAUAGUUGUAGGUAAAGAAAGGCAGAUAUAUUAGAGAACGUAUGAAAAUACGUUGCAAGGAAGCAAUGGGCAGCACAGCAGAGAAGGGGCUGUCUGCAAGGAGACAAAGGCGUGCUGGAGAUUUUACAGGAUGGUGCUUGUACUGUGUGCUGAAGAGGGUUUGUGUGGUACUGAUAACACUAAGGUUGCAGUGAGCUAAGUUACAUUUUUCUAUCAGCUGAAGGUCUGGUGAUAGCUGGGUGCAGGAAUAUUGUGCAGGAGGGCUAUGUGUCCUGGACCAUGAAGAAGGUGAGUCUUAUACAUUACCUGCUUUCUUUCUUUGUUUUUUGUUUUUUGGUUUUUUUUAUUUAUUUAUCACAUUGUGCAGGUUAGUUAUAUAUGUAUACAUGUGCCAUACUGGUGCGCUGCACCCACUAACUUGCUUUCCUCUGGUCCUGCCAGCCUGACUUCUUUUCCCUAAGGAGGACUCCACAGAAAUGAAUUCUGGGUGAUUUCUAUAUUCUACGAUGGAGACUAUAGCUAUAGAUCAUUAUACAACACUACCUAAUUAAUCAAGACCAAAAUAAAUAGUCCUACCUGCAGGACAAUAACCAGUAACAAAUAAUUUACAAUUAGAAAUUAGUUCCAGACAGAAGGAAAUAUUUCUUAUUUUACCUGCACUUACAUGACUGCAUUUUAGCUAACUGGAGCCUGUGAUGGACAACCAAAACAUGGGUUUUCUUCACAGAUAUUUUUCUUUUGACUCAUUAGGUUACUGUGAAAAGAUAAUUUUCUUUCAGAGAUUUGUAAUUUUUCAGAAGUGUUUUUGAAUCCUUGAACUCAUAUUUGUUGCAGAGCAGCGUCAAUAUACCAUGAGACACUCUAAGAACUUUUUGCAUAAGUGUUGAUGUGUAAAGAGAAUCACUAAAUUCAAACCCAGCUCUGCCCAGGGAGUAAUAAAUCCUAAGAGACUAUUUUAACUCACUUACAUAUGUUCUUCUGGUUUGGUUUGGUUUGGUUUCUACUAUCAGGUACCUAGGAAGUAGCACUCAAGAUUAGGAGAAAAAAUAAGUUUAUUCUGGAUCAAAAAUUUUUUAACUUUUUCAGAUUAAUCUGUUUUUUUCCUAUAAUGUUCUUAAAAAUUCUAGAGACAAUUUUCUCUAUGCACCUUUGAAAAUGAAAUAAAUGUAACGACUAAAACCAAGCAAAGUGAAAUAGAUUAUCCUUCACAAUGGAGGUGAAAUCCAAGAGAUAAUUCAAAAAAAUUACGUAUCUCAAGUUCCUGUCUGUCAGAUUUGGCACCAGAGAUUUCAUCCAGUGGAAUUACUGAUUUGGAACCUAAAUAGAAUUUUAUUUUCCAAGUUCCAGUAUUUUCAAUUUUCAUGAAAUUCAGGCCUUCAUAAAUAAAUAAAUAGGAGAAAACAGGCUCUACAUCUCAGAAGAAAAGAUUCCUGUGGGUUCCUUGCCCCUACUCUGAAGUAUAAUCAUUAAGGAAUUCCCAAGGGACUAAAAGGUUAUAACUUAGAAUUUAUAUUUCACUCUUAUUAGGAAUACAGGUAAAAUAGUAUAACUUAUCUAACAAUAAGCAAUGAGAAAUGUGGAGAAGGCAAGUUUCAGGAAAUCAAAGAUCAUAAUUCCAGCUCUAACCAAUUUAUAUUUUAGCCUGCAGAAAAACAAGUUAUUCCUAUCAGUUAUGUAAAGUGACUUUUCCAUUUGUACGCAGGUAGACAUGGUUUGCACACACACACACACUUUAAACCCAAUAUAUAGCUCACUCCUCCAGUCUUUAUCAGCACAUGCUCUGAGAUCACAAAAAGCAUUGAAAGAUUACUAAUCACACUGACCAUUUUUAUGGUGGUGGCACAAACAAAUAAUUGUCAUUUUGUGAGCUGUAAUACUAAUUUUAAAAGGGGACACAAGCAAUCAAUCCACAGAAUCAAAAUCUGUGGACAUAUUAUUUUCCUGAUUUGUAAUGAGUUGUAUCUAUAAUUAUUCAUUGGCCAAAUUUUCUCUUUCUUUUAUUAUUCUGUCAAAAGCACAAUGCUUCCUAUGACGAUUUUCUGAAAUAAGUGUUUUGUCUUGCACAUGGAAAUGGUGUGGGUCCUGCUUUGGUAACCUAAAGUUAUCCCUAUUUUAUGAGGCAUAAAACUCUUCCUCAGUAAAUAAACAACUCUAAUGAGAUGUUUGUACGAAAACUGGCACCAUCAGUGAUAAAGAAAACAUCCGGUGCAGUCUGUAAACACCCAUUUUGGGGGGUUAUAAAACUCUCAGGAGAGGAGAGUUUUGGAGUCAAGGCAACUGAAGUUUUGCAGCCAGUCUCUGUCUUUGCUUCUGGAAGGAUGACUUCUGACUGCUCCUCCACACACUGCUCUCCUGAGUCCUGUGGCACGGCUUCCGGUUGUGCACCUGCCUCAAGCUGCUCCGUGGAAACAGCUUGUCUCCCCGGUACCUGUGCUACAUCCCGAUGUCAGACUCCAAGCUUCCUAUCCAGGUCUCGCGGGCUGACUGGUUGCCUCCUGCCAUGCUACUUUACUGGGAGUUGUAAUAGUCCCUGCUUGGUGGGGAACUGUGCCUGGUGUGAGGAUGGGGUGUUCACUAGCAAUGAGAAGGAGACGAUGCAGUUCCUGAAUGACAGACUCGCCAGCUAUCUGGAGAAGGUGCGCAGCCUGGAGGAGACCAACGCAGAGCUGGAAUCCAGGAUCCAAGAACAAUGUGAACAGGAUAUCCCAAUGGUGUGCCCGGAUUAUCAGCGUUACUUCAACACCAUUGAAGAUCUCCAACAAAAGAUCUUAUGCACGAAAGCAGAGAAUUCUAGACUUGCUGUACAGCUUGACAACUGCAAACUGGCCACUGAUGACUUUAAGUCAAAGUACGAGAGUGAACUGUCCCUUCGCCAGCUGUUAGAGGCUGACAUCAGCAGCCUGCAUGGGAUCCUGGAGGAACUGACCCUGUGCAAAUCUGAUCUGGAGGCCCAUGUGGAGUCUCUGAAGGAAGAUCUCCUUUGCCUUAAGAAAAACCAUGAAGAGACGAAGAAACUGAGGCCCUUCUAAGUGGUGAAAAGAGAUUCAGCCCAGGCAAUCUGAAUCAAAAUCUCACACUUUUACCCACUGCUCCAAAAAACAGAAGUAGAAUGCCAUUGGAUGUCAAAUGGAUUUUUCCCCACCAUUCUGUGACAUUCUUUACACCAUCCCACUUUCAGGAAGUCAACUUGCUUCGUGAACAGCUUGGCGACCGCCUCAGUGUGGAGCUGGACACUGCCCCCACCCUUGACCUCAACAGGGUCCUGGAUGAGAUGCGCUGUCAGUGUGAAACGGUGCUUGCCAACAAUCGCAGAGAAGCUGAAGAAUGGUUGGCUGUUCAGGUCAGUACCCAGAUUGAAAAAAUGUCAGGCUUACAGACUUCUGCCUUUUUUGAAUUCUCUAAUGGUGUCUGUGUUUCAGACAGAAGAGCUGAAUCAGCAGCAACUGUCCAGCGCGGAGCAGCUGCAGGGCUGCCAGAUGGAGAUCUUGGAACUGAAACGCACAGCCAGUGCUCUGGAAAUUGAGCUCCAAGCACAGCAAAGCCUGGUGCGUGAGGCAAAGGCAGUGUCCGUUGUGUCACUGAUAAGUCAGGCCCUGAGAUGUUAAGCCCUCUUCCAUAUCCGAGGAUCACAUUUCCUUGCCUUUCCCGAGUACUGCCGUUUACCCAGCUAUUAAUAGAAGCAGAAGUGACAGGUCCACAGCUUGUCCUCUAAGAUGCCUUACCUUCACUCCUGGGCUUGAGUCUGAUGCUGCAGCAGCCUCCAGAGACAGGGAGGGAGAAGCAGAGCUGGAGAGAAACCUCCGGGCCAUGGUCGCUUAAGCAUUCUGGCAGGUUUUAAUUCUCAUUUGAUUCAGGCCAGUUUUCCAGGCUCACUGUUAUAUCUAAAACAAAGAAUCAUUUUCAAACAUUUCAUCCUACAGUUUCCCAGGAUCUACACUUCAACCUUAUCCUUCACUGCACCACCCCCCACUCAAGCAACAGGAACACCAUGCGUUCAAGAUGACAUGAACCAGUUCUGGUCAAGCACCACUGUGUGCAUGUCAUUAGGCCCUGCGGAGAACACCUAGAAGAACAAUAGCUGAGCAUUCAUCCUGUGAGAGGCACUAUGCUGAUUUAAGGCUCACAGUAACUUUACCGGAUAGAUACCUUUAUCCCAUGACACAGAUAAGGAAAACUGAGACUCAGAUUAAGUAACUUGCAAAGGAUGCAAUUCUAAGAGGCAAACUUGGAAGCUGAGUUCAGCCAGUUGAAUCCCAGAGUCUCUUCUCUCUCUCUUUUUAAAUUUAUUUUUAUUGAUAUAUAAUAUGCGUAAAUUUUUUUUACGUAGAUGUGAUAUUUUGUUACAUGCAUAGAAUGUGUAAUGAUCAAGUCAGGAUAUUUAGAGCAUCCAUCACCUCAAGUAUUUAUCAUUUCUAUGUGUUGGGAGCAUUUCAAGUCCUCCCAUCUAGCUAUUUUGAAAUGCACAGUGUAUUGUUGUUAACUGUAGUCACACUUCUCUGCUGUCCAACAUGAAAACAUAUUCUUUCUGUCUAACUGUAUGUUUGCACCCAUUAACCAACCUCUCUUCAUCCCCUUACCACACAUAUGCCAGUCCCAGCCUCUGGUAUCCAGAGCCUCUUCUCUUAAUAGCACUAUACUACCCCUCCCUGCCAAGAGCCCAAACUCAAUCUUUCCUCUCAUAUGUUGUGGAUAGUCCUUAAGCUUCACAAAUAUGUCAUGUAUUGCUGUAGUCAUAGUGGUGGUAGUGAUAGUUGACACGUAGAACAGUGGCAGUAUGGCUGGCACUGUUCUAAAUGCUUUACGCACAUUAACUCUUUUUUUUUUUUUUUGGACGGAGUCUCCCUCUGUCGCCCAGGCUGGAGUGCAAUGGCAUGAUCUUGACUUACUGCAAGCUUUGCCUCCCGGGUUCACACCAUUCUCCUGAGUAGCUGGGACUACAGGCGUCCACCACCGUACCCAGCUAAUUUUUUAUAUUUUUAGUAGAGACGGGGUUUCACCGUGUUAGCCAGGAUGGUCUCGAUCUUCUGACCUUGUGAUCCGCCCGCCUCGGCCUCCCAAAGUGCUGGGAUUACAGGCCUGAGCCACCGCGCCCAGCCCGCAUAUUAACUCUUAAUCUUCACAACCGUCUAAUGAAACAGAUACUUUGUAUUCUCCACUAUACAGAGAAUAAAACUGAGACUCACAGAAGCUAAAUAAUUUGCCAGUGGUCACAUAGCUAGAAAAGGGUAAGCAGGAAUUUGAAAGUAGGCACUCUGGCCCGAGAGACUGCACUUCAUGGUCCUUUGGACAAUGUUUCCUCCCGCAGACAGAAUCUCUGGAAUGCACCGUGGCAGAAACCGAGGCCCAGUACAGCUCCCAGCUGGCCCAAAUUCAGUGUCUGAUCGAUAACCUGGAGAACCAGCUGGCCGAGAUCCGCUGCGACCUGGAGCGACAGAACCAGGAGUACCAGGUGCUCCUGGACGUGAAGGCCCGGCUGGAGGGUGAGAUCAACACGUACUGGGGCCUGCUGGACAGCGAGGACAGCAG